AUCCUCUCCCUCGGAGUCAGCUGGUGGAGGAGAGGAAGCGGGAGGAGGGAGCGCGCGCGAGGGGAGGAGAGGAAUGUGCAGGUCCGAGGAGCGCCGCGGCGGCCGCUGCUGCUCCUGCUGCUGGCGGCGGCGGCGGCUCGGGCGGCAGCAGCGAAGCCGGGACGGCGAGGAGCGCGGGCGGCGGGCAGGGGCGCGCGCGGGGCGCCGCGAGCAGCUUGGCUCCGCGCAGGCAGCCAGGCGGCGCUCCUGCCGGCCCCAGGCGCGCCGCUAGCCCGGCCCAGCGCCCAGCCCGGCGGGCGGCGGGCGGCGGCGGACGGCAGGCGAGCCGACGCAGGAGCAGGAGGAGGGGGAGCCGCACCGCCUGGGAGGGAAGCCGGGGCGAGGCGAGGAGGUGGCGGGAGGAGGAGACAGCGGGGAAAGGUGUCAGAUAAAGGAGGGCUCUCCUCCGGUGUGGAGGCAUCAUGGCCGCUAAAUCAGACGGGAGGCUGAAAAUGAAGAAAAGCAGCGACGUGGCGUUCACCCCGCUGCAGAACUCGGACCACUCGGGCUCGGUGCAGGGAUUGGCUCCAGGCUUGCCGUCGGGGUCGGGAGCCGAGGACGAGGAGGCGGCCGGGGGCGGCUGCUGCCCGGACGGCGGCGGCUGCUCGCGCUGCUGCUGCUGCUGCGCCGGGAGUGGCGGCUCCGCGGGCUCGGGCGGCUCCGGCGGCGUCGCCGGCCCGGGCGGCGGCGGGGCGGGCUCGGCUGCGCUGUGCCUGCGCCUGGGCAGGGAGCAGCGGCGCUACUCACUGUGGGACUGCCUCUGGAUCCUGGCCGCCGUGGCCGUGUACUUCGCGGACGUGGGCACAGACGUCUGGCUCGCCGUGGACUACUACCUGCGCGGCCAGCGCUGGUGGUUCGGGCUCACGCUCUUCUUCGUGGUGCUCGGCUCUCUGUCGGUGCAAGUGUUCAGCUUCCGCUGGUUUGUGCACGAUUUCAGCACCGAGGACAGCGCCACGGCCGCUGCUGCCUCCAGCUGCCCGCAGCCUGGAGCCGAUUGCAAGACGGUGGUCGGCGGUGGGUCUGCAGCCGGGGAAGGCGAGGCUCGUCCUUCCACGCCGCAAAGGCAAGCAUCUAACGCCAGCAAGAGCAACAUCGCCGCGGCCAACAGCGGCAGCAACAGCAGCGGGGCUACCCGGGCCAGUGGCAAGCACAGGUCUGCGUCCUGCUCCUUCUGCAUCUGGCUCCUGCAGUCACUCAUCCACAUCUUGCAGCUCGGGCAAAUCUGGAGAUAUUUCCACACAAUAUACUUAGGUAUUCGAAGCCGACAGAGUGGGGAGAAUGACAGAUGGAGGUUUUACUGGAAAAUGGUAUAUGAGUAUGCGGAUGUGAGUAUGCUGCAUUUGCUAGCCACCUUUCUGGAAAGUGCUCCACAGCUGGUCCUGCAGCUCUGCAUUAUCGUACAGACUCAUAGCUUACAGGCCCUCCAAGGUUUCACAGCGGCAGCUUCCCUCGUGUCCCUGGCCUGGGCCUUGGCCUCCUACCAGAAGGCCCUCCGGGACUCUCGAGAUGACAAGAAGCCCAUCAGCUACAUGGCCGUCAUCAUCCAGUUCUGCUGGCACUUCUUCACCAUCGCCGCCAGGGUCAUCACGUUUGCCCUCUUUGCCUCGGUUUUCCAGCUGUACUUUGGGAUCUUCAUCGUCCUUCACUGGUGCAUCAUGACCUUCUGGAUCGUCCACUGUGAGACAGAAUUCUGUAUCACCAAAUGGGAAGAGAUUGUGUUCGACAUGGUGGUGGGGAUUAUCUAUAUCUUCAGUUGGUUCAAUGUCAAGGAAGGCAGGACACGCUGCAGGCUAUUCAUUUACUAUUUUGUGAUCCUUUUGGAAAAUACAGCCUUGAGUGCCCUCUGGUACCUCUACAAGGCUCCCCAGAUUGCAGACGCAUUUGCCAUUCCAGCGCUGUGUGUGGUGUUCAGCAGCUUUUUAACUGGCGUUGUUUUUAUGCUGAUGUAUUAUGCCUUCUUUCAUCCCAAUGGACCCAGAUUCGGGCAGUCACCAAGUUGUGCUUGUGAGGACCCAGCCGCUGCCUUCACUUUGCCCCCAGACGUGGCCACAAGCACCCUACGGUCCAUCUCCAACAACCGCAGUGUUGUCAGCGACCGCGAUCAGAAAUUCGCAGAGCGGGAUGGGUGUGUACCUGUCUUUCAAGUGAGGCCCACUGCCCCAUCCACCCCAUCAUCUCGCCCACCACGGAUUGAAGAAUCAGUCAUUAAAAUUGACUUGUUCAGGAAUAGGUACCCAGCAUGGGAGAGACAUGUUUUGGACCGAAGCCUCCGAAAGGCUAUUUUAGCUUUUGAAUGUUCCCCAUCUCCUCCAAGGCUGCAGUACAAAGAUGAUGCCCUUAUUCAGGAGCGGUUGGAGUACGAAACCACUUUAUAAAGCAAAAGGAGUUGCAGGACCCACAACAUCCAGAUGAAGGGGUGACAGCAGGGCUGUGGCCAUAAUGACACUUCAUCCUAGAGCAGGGCAGUGAGCCGUGAAGUUCCUAGUGGGACCGUCAUCACCAUUAUCAUUUGAUCCUGUCGGCUGGGGGCGGCUGGUCUCCUUCCAAAGCAGCUGCACCCGAGAGUCUCUGACUCCACCUGAAAGAAUGACGCUGGCUUAAUAGGACUCUCCAUUGCUACCAAACUCCUCCUGCACGGUCUUGGGUGCACCCACCAGAGGGUACUACUAUUAUGGAAAAAUUUUGCCUCCAAUCAUUAGGGUGUCUUGAUGGCGUUAACUGAUCUUUCCAUAAAAAUAGAUUCAGUCAUACACACAUACACACACUAACACACAUAAGUUACACCAGUCCUCUGUCAAAAAAGCUUAGGUGACUUUUCUUGAUGCAAAGCUCUGAUUCCCACAGGAAUAUAAAAACAAAGAAAGAGGGAAACAUCCCUCGAGAAAAAAAAUAGUAUUGCUUAGAAAAGAAACCAUUUUCUCAUUUGGAAAUCCAUACCAUGUGUGAAAAUCCUAUCCAACGGACAGCAAACCCAAAUGUUGUCUACACAUGUGUUAGCAUUGAUGGAGUGGUUCAUUUUCUACACAUUUCAGGAUUUGUUUUAUAUUUUAAAUUUUCAGUUGCGAACAUCCUUUUUGACAGAAAUCCUAUGCAGCCCAUGUACGGCUUUCAACAAGACCAAGGAGCUCAAUAACUUCAUGAUGUAAAUUAAAUAGUAAUCAUGAUUCAGUAUUCAAUUGCAAAAAUGUAACAGGUACACAAAGAGGAAGUGGGGAAAAAGGCAAAAUGAGAGUCUGAUUCCCAGGCAUGUGCAGCGCCCAUUGGGACAUAACGGCAGUGCGGCGCGAGCCAGAGGAAUGGGCUGGAACCGGAUCUGUUUCCAGACGCAGAAUGAGUGGCUCUGUGUGACCAUAGGCAGAUGCUGACUCUGGAAGACUCCGUGCCACUCCUUUCUAGUGCCAAACACCAUCCAACCACAGGACUGACGUGGAAGCCCCAAACAACUGAGAAUGAGUGGCAUGAGCCCCCUAAAAGCAGGCGAGAGAACGAGCAAUCAAGUUCUCCACUGUGUACAGACUUUUCCUCCCCCCAAUCCAAGGUCAAAGUGAUGUGUCUUUUAGAGGCUUUGGGACACUUUUUAGUAAGUAUGAGCAGACAAAUGCAAUGAAUAUGCUAUGAAAAAACCCUUCUGAACUGAGAGAGGGCUUAUCACUAUAUCCAGCUAAGAUUUGUAUUUGAAUCAUCUGUAAAGUCGCACUCUUACAACAAGCUUCUGGGUUUUAAAUACCUCCGUACAGCAAGUAAACGUUCCCCGCUUUCUGUUCUCAGUGUCCUCGGUCAUGGUGCUUUUCGUUGCAUUAAAAGUGCCGGUCAAACUUUGAUAGUAUUUUUUUAUAGUUGGUGCAGAGUGGAAUAACUCAUGGAUUAUUUCAAUAUUUUUGUAAUAAAAAAUAUAGGGUAUACACAUAGGCAUCAUCACAUUUUUUAUAGACCUGGAAUCGUUUAAAAUACUUUAAGCAUCAUAAUUACUUGGGAUGUCAGAAACUGGUCCACAAAUUCCAUCAGCCUGCCUCAGCAGAUUGAAAACAUUUGUCUCUUGCAAGAUCACCCUACUUUGCAAGUUGGUGCCCCCAGGAACCUGGCCAGGGGUGCUAUCAGAAUAUCAGGUGAAGAGAGAAUCAGCUUAAAUAGAAAGGGCUUGUCAAGACUGGCCAAUGUUUCCCAGGAAAUCAAAGAUGUAAAUGAUUACUUUCAUCCAUCCAUUAUAACAAACCUGACCACAGUGGAAGCUGUCUUAAACUUCCUUCCCUGGUUUUAUAUUAACCCAACUGAUAGAUUAAGUAUUAGUCAAACCACUAAAAAAGAAAAAGAAAAAAGUUUAACUUAAUUAUUCGGUUAUUUGGAUCUAAUUCACACAAAGUAGUCCAGUUCUCUAGCCACCACCUGUAAUGGGUGUGUCAUCCAGAGACUGUGUCCCCACGAUGACAUCCACAGGAAGUAACAGAGGGCUCAACCUAGGACUUCUUUUGGUACAAAGCCCCAAAUCAAUUUUUUUAAAAAAUAGACAAUUUUUAUAAGUAGACAUACUUCCUAGUACUCCAUGAUUUGAUCCUCCAAGCAAGAUUUCCACUAAAAAAUACUAAUCUUUUGUUGGGAUGUGGAAAGAUUACCUAGUCACCAGUAAAGGCCCAGGAAAAGGCUCUUCUUGUCAGCACAUGGUGAAAACAUUCCAUCCCCACUGGAGAAGGAAAAAACGAUUUUGGCAAAUUCUUCACUUUUGUGCAGAACCUUGAGUUAUUAGCUUCAUUGUUUCCAAGACAACUUUUAACUGAUGAUCUUUGGAAAUUGAGUUUCUCAGUUGAACUGUACCUUUGAUUCUAUGAGUAAAUCACAGAUUACAGUCUAAUAGAGUCAAUCAAUCAACACAAACCCAACAGGCCCCAUCAUGCUUCAAUCAUGUAAGUUCUAAGUUAUUUCUCAACUUGAUCCCUCAUUCAACAUGUUAAGAGUCAGAAUGAAUACUAUGUCAAUGAAAAAUGAUGUACUGUGCUUUGACUUGGAGGUGAGAUUGGCAGUCAGGAGAAUGUAAGGAGGUUGAAUUUUUCAGUGAUUUCCCAAAUACUGUAAAUACUCUGUUAUCCGACAUAUUUGGAGAUUAUGAUGUUUUAAUUAGGCAUGAAUUCUUGUUAAGGAAAGAACAUAUCCAUGAUGUGAUGAAUUACAACCUUUCAAAAGAUUACAAGAGCAAAACAAGAGAUAAAUCAUGAUUUAGCCUUGCUUCCAUGAUUCAGGAAGCACUACACUGCCAUCAGACUGUUGUGGUAAUAACAACUUUUACUUGUUUUCUAGAUGCACAGAUAACAGAGAGUUUAAAGUAUUCAGAUUUAAAGAGACAUCAUCAGUGUACAAAGAAACAAAGUUUCAUUUUUGUAUUUAUAUUUUAAUUCUAACAUUUCCUUUUCAAUCUGCCAUUAAACCCUCCGCAGACAGUAACUGGAGAAUCCCAAAGGAAAAAAUUGGAAAUGCUGGGUUCCUUAUCUGCAGGCUCCUUUCUGUGUCUGAGUCCACUUUGAUUCCAUUUAAGAGGGAGAUCUGCUCUUACUCACUUUUUGCAUAGGAUCAGGAAAUUUUCUAAAGGAACAACAUUGUAAUUUGUUUUACUUUUAAACUUGCAUUUCUAAAUAUGAAACCAUGUUUAAUGAAUAUAUAUAAUGUGUGUGUGUGUAUCUUAACCAUAGUGACACUUUAAGUGUUUGUGUGAAAGAAAAGGAAAUAAUUUUUCCAUGUAAGUCAAAGUUUAGUCUCCCAAAAUGACUAUGUCCUUUAAAUCCUCUUUGCUUAUUUACUUAACUACAUACUGUCUAGUUCAAUAGCACUGACUUUGCAGACACUUAGUUACUACUCAUUUGUGAUAAACGCUGUUAACCCAACAAAUAUAAUAAAUUCUCUUACUGACAUGGCAAGAAUAUAUAAUUCAAGUAUUAGCAAAAGAUAAUCUGAGGAUAAAAGUAAAAUGAAGUAUUUUAUGGUUAAUUUCUAAAUGCCCAAUUUAUUUUGCUCUAUGAGUAAAGGAAGUGAUUGCACAGAACAAUUAAAAGUGAAUGAGAAUAGUUGAAAACUCAAUGGCUGUUUUUUAAAAAUGAUAUGUGCCUUUUAAGUGUGUUUGUGUACAUACAUAUAUGUAUAUAUACGUACCUAUAUAUGUAUGUACACACACACACACACACACUUUCCAACUAAAGUAACAGAGAUGAAAAGGAUAAAGUAUAUACUGCUUUUGAAUGUAUAUAAAGUGGUAUGUUAUGCAUAUAAAUUGUACAUAAACUUUUUAGAAAAGAAGCAUUUUCCUGCUCCUUUUUCAAAACCAACCCAAGCUUACAGUCCAUCUAUAAGACCAACACACUUACGAACUUCAGUUGGAAAUACCUAAAUAUAAUUCAGCACUUCUUAGCUCGAAUGAGUUUUAUCACUUCUUAAGGAUCUCAUCUUUUAAACAGCUGAAUAAAAUAGUUCUGUGUCACUUCAAAGUUUCUUUCUCUGAACAGAUUGAAUUGAGCAAAGAGAACCUCUUCUGUCCUUACCAGGAUUGUGUAAGGUUACACAUUUGCUUUUAAAUAUACCAAAUGCCGUUGAUUGGAAACAAGUUCUGACACAAUGUUUAGACAAGAAUCCAGAGAUUUUUUCUAAUGAACCAUUUUCUAGACUAAAUAUAUGCUCCCUUGCAUUUUCCACAUAUCUUUGCCAUUAGCCAUUGCUGUUUCUAUAUAAAGCUUGGAUGAGAUGCCUGCAUUUUUAUGUGCUAAGGAGAAUUCCUUAAAGCCUUUUUAAAAAUAGCUCAUACUGUCAUUCAGAUUAUAGCUCAGAGGAUGGUUGAAGCGCAUGGUGAAAACACAGGAGGACUGGGGUGGUCAUUCCUAUAAUUUCAGUGACAGAUGCAGAUCAACGUUCCUUUGUCUCGGCAAUCCAAUGUCAUUUUUGAAAACAAUCAAAAAGAUCGCUUGUGUCAGCUUCUGACUCAUAACACUCCUCCCACCUGAUGCUCCAGUGUUUCAAAAUGGCCAAGGAUGGGCGAUUCCGCUCUAUCCCCCAUUUCUGAGACUCUUGUCUGGACCUGUAACAGGCCGUGAAAUGCCCUGAGCAUUCGAGUGGCAUCCCUUCUCCUCACAUAGGCACCUGGGUGGCAGCAUCAGACCACUGAAGUUGUUGUGUUGACAUAUGUCUUAUCUAGUUGCUGUCCUAAAAAUGGGCAUGUGGCAAGACUCUCAAUCUACAGCCUCGACAGUAUCAUUACUCAUUCUAAAGUAAAACUGCAGAAUAUGGGUGGAAUUGUAUAAAAACAUAAUGAGCCAUUUAAUUUUGCUAAUUGAAGCAAUUAGUCUAACAUGCAAGCAGCCUGCUCUCACAGCAGAGAGCCACAUGGAAGAAGUGCCAAAUAGCCAUUUGCAUUUAUAUAUAUAUAUUGCAGGCAGUGACCUGGCCCCCAAAUGUAAAGCUUUUGUCAACCUUGAGGCCUAUAUUCUGCUAAACAAGAGAUGACUUAAUGUCCUUGAAAUAUUUUCGUAAUAUACUGACAGCCUAAUGUCAGAAACGAGCUGCCUAAAUCAAGUUUUGCUUUUGGUUAUUUCACUUCCCCAUAGACUUUCUUAUGGUUCCAUCUCCCACAUUGAGAGUAGCUCACCACGAUGGAUGGUUUACUGCGCACCUAGUGCUGGACUAAGAGCUGUAUCUAUGUGGUUUCAUUUAGUCCUCACUGCCAUCUGUGAGUUAAGCAUCAUUUACAGAUGACAAAAUCUGUAAAUGGCUUAGAGAUGUCAAGCAAUUUGCCCAAAGGUCCCACAGCUAGGAAACAGUGGGGCUGAGGGUUGAGCACAGCUUUCAACAACUGCGACUUCUGGGAGCCCAGUGACUCUUCCCACAAAAUCUAGUCCUGAUUUGGCAAGUCUUCAGAAGAAACAGAAUCAUGGUCUGAUGAUCAAAUUUUUCCAAGAAAAUUUUAUUUAAAAGUCAAAGAUGUCCUUCAAAAUGAACAGUUAAAAAUGUAAAAGUCGAUGUAAAAUGGAAGUCUCUAUCACCUGUAACUAAAUUUUACCUUAACUCUAACUCAUAGUAGGCAGAUAAAUGCUAUUCUUCCAUUCCAGGCAACUGUCCCCCUCCUAUGGCUCCACUAUGUAUUCAAUUAAGUGAUAAAUAUAAAUUAACCUGAUGCCAUGUCUCUUGUAUUUUAUAUGUGUAUGCUGUUUUCAUCCAAUUAAGCAGACUGAAAAAAAACUAAACCCCAUUACUUACUUUGGCAUUUUGACAAGAUAGAGAGAGAGGAAAAGAAAGAGGGAGGGAGAGAGGGAGGGAAGGAAGAAGGAAGGAAGGAAGGAAGGAAGGAAGGAAGGAAGGAAGGAAGGAAGGAAGGAAGGAAGGAAGGAGAUUUAACAAGUCUUUGAAGUGAUAUUUUCAAAUUAUAAGGUAAUUCUGUUUCACUGCCAUAAUUUUUCCCUAAAUUUUAUUUAAUAUCUUGCAGGUCACAAACUUUAAUAUUUAAGAGGAUUAUUAAACCACUAGCUUGAACAAUCAUAUAAGUCUAGGAACCUUAUUUUAGUGUUAGAUGCCAAUAAUACUGCAAGUGUCAACCAAAUAUUUGUUGAAUUGAAUUAUAAAAUAAUUGAUGUGUUCUUUCCCUUCUCACUUUAGAUAUAGCAUGUCUGAAGGUCUGCAAGAUGACAGAGUUGUAACCCAUUCAAUGAUAUUGUUGCCUAGUAAGCUGUGUGUGUGUUGUUUGAACUGAUACUAAAAAGGUAGCUGAUAAUAAACCAAAAAUUUUCUCAACCCUGGUGUUUAUUUUUAAAAAAUCUUCAAUGAUCAAUAUGAAUGUAGUGUAUUAAAAUACAAGUAACUAUCUUCCUACUUUGAUUUAAGAGAUCUUUAUGAAUUUAUAUAAAAUUAGAAGUCACUGAUUUUUAUAGGAAAUAGCAUGUAAAAUAAAUCUAAGUAUUGCUUUAUCACUUUAUUUUAUAGAUGAGACAACUGAGAUCCAAAAAGAACAGGUAAUUUUUGUGAUCAGGAUUACACAAUACACUUUUUUUUUUCCCUGAGUCAUUUAUUCAACAAGUUUGACCUCUACAACUCAUUUGGCUAGGCAAUGCACAGUCAAGCACAAAAGGAAAGUUGCACUGGAAUAGCUCAUAGUCUGGCUAUUAGCAGCACAAUCAUAGUUUUCUGACGCCAGCUCUUACUCUUUUCUACUCUACCACACUGUUUCUUCUCUUCUCAAUAUCUAUAUUUAAUUCCAUAUUGAAGCAAGAAAGAAACACAGCUUUUCUAAGACUAUGCAGUCAUGUGUCACUUAAGGAUGGGGAUAUGUUCUGAGAUAUGCAUCGUCAGGCAAUUUUGUCAUUGUGUGAUGGAGUGUGCUUACACAAGCUUAGAUGGUAGAGCCUACCAUGCUCCUAGGCUAUAUGGUAGAGCCUAUUGUCCCUAGGCUACAAACCUGUACAGCAUGCUACUGUACCGAAUACUGUAGGCAACUGUAACACCAUGGUAAGUACUUGUGUAUUUAAAUAUAGAAAAGUUAACAGUAAAAAAUAUAGUAUUAUUGUCUUAUGGGAUCGCUGUCAUAUGUGCAGUCUAUUAUUGACCAAAAUGCCAUUGUGUGGCAUGUGAGCCUUACAAUAUACAAUUAACAUAUGAAAUAAUGAUGAUGAACAUAAAGUAACAAUACAAAUACAAAAAAAAAACUAGAUGACUGCUUAUAAAGAGAAAAGUAAUUUUAUAAUUUGUUUAUAUGACUCUCCAACACUAGAUAUUUUUAAAUUGAUAUCACAACACACAAAAAAAUUGAAAUACUCUCUUGGUGCAUAGUAUUUGAUUGAAAACAAUCAUUUUUGGAUAAACUUUGAAGCGAUUCUUGAGAACUUAUUUCAAGAAAAGGCAUGAAAUUAGGGAGACUCCAAAGUGAAGAGUUUUCCAAUAGGUGACUUCUCUGAUUUUUCAAGAAAGCAUUCUUCACUAACUGUAUUUCUCCAGCAUACUGGUUAUUUAGGAAUAACAAAUUUCUGGACAUAAACAUGAGCUGUUUCUCUAAAGCCUUUCCUCCAAUGCCCAGAAGAGCAGCACUGUGCUGCGUGACAAUUUCAGGAGUCAGGAGUCAGGAGUCAGGACAGUCAGCCCCAGCUUCCUGGGGAAACCCACACUGGCUUUGGACCCGAUUGCAUUCUCUCCUGAGUGAUUGGCUUCCCACAUAUAUAAGCAGCAGAUUGUUAAAGAUCACUAUUAACUUGUAUAACUAAUUUUCCUUAUGUGAAAUAAUUCUGGUCAGGGAAUAUAUAAACCCAUUGGCCCUCUAAGGAGUAGAAGAAAAGAGAGAAGAAAGUAUAUUAACUUUUAUGAGUACAGAAUAAUUCAAGUUCCUUAGCGAGUCACAUUAUGCAUUAAUAAAAGAGUUGACCUAAUAAAUGUUACAAGGUACCAUGAUCUCUAGGUUCAUGCCACCAUUACCACAUUCCUUACUACAAUUAUUGCUAUUUUAGUCAUUGGACCAGACAAAAUGAAGCAUAUAAUUACUGAUAUAAUAUUUGCUAAGCAAAAAUCUUGUUUAACGAAAAAAAUCAAUACCAAAACUAAUUAAUCAAAAUAUUAAGCAAAUAUUACCAGCACAGUACUGACACAAAAUUUUCUCUUGUGCUAGUAAUUGAAGUAUGUCAUCUACCCUGUUAUUAGAAUUUCAGAAAAUAGGCCGGGCGCAGUGGCUCACGCCUGUAAUCCCAACACUUUGGGAGGCUGAGGCGGGCGGAUCACAAGGUCAGGAGAUCGAGACCAUCCUGGCUAACACAGUGAAACCCCCAUCUCUACUAAAACUACAAAAAAAUUAGCCAGGCAUGGUGGCGGGCGCCUGUGGUCCCAGCUACUCGGGAGGCUGAGGCAGGAGAAUGGCAUGAACCCAGGAGGCAGAGCUUGCAGUGAGCCAAGAUCGUGCCACUGCACUCCAGCCUGGGUGACAGAGCAAGACUCCGUCUCAAAAAAAAAAAAAAAAAAAAAAAAGAAUUUCAGAAAAUAUAAAGUUUUAUGUUUUUAUUAUAUUUCCAUCUACCAAAUUGUUGACCUUCUCCUCCUCUCCAUUGCUUAAUUUAUAUUAAAACAGAUUUAAUCAAAUUAUUACUUAAGUACUACAAAUGUUAUCAGAUGGAGAUGUGGUUAAGCUAAUUUAAUUUACCUAUUCUAGUGGCAUUCUGGUAUGGAGCUGUAUCAAAUCAACACUUUUAAUUAUUUCACAUUAAUUCAUCAAGAAGUUCCAAAACACUACUAAAUGUGUUGAAAAUAUAGUUUGAGUUUCUAUGAUUGUAAUCAAAAUUCCUAUUUUGAUCGCACACCAGUAGAACGCAUCUUAACACCAGCAUUGCCAUUGUGAGUCUAGAAAAUGAGCACUUUGUGUGUUGAGCGCUGUUGCAUUCACUUAGCAAUUAACCUUUGACCUGUGGUUUUCUGCUGAGCCCCUUGUGAUUUUUUUUAUUCUAUUCAAAUUGGGAGCAAUAACACACCUUAACAUAACCAAAAAAAGGAGACCUGUCAGCUAGUGAAAGAAUUGUCAUUUUAUAUCAUUCUUUCAAAAAAUUAAAAUAUUCAACUUCCCUUAUUAACCUUUCUAAUGCAUUGUACAUAAAAGAGGAAAUGGAUUUCUGAAAUAUAUUUUGAAAGCCUGGGGUGAAACAUUUUCCACGGUCUGAAUCGGAAGCUUGGGGCUCUGUGGAAAGAUGUAAAUCCCUCCUGCUGUAAGAGGAGGGAAGGCAGCAGUGAGCUGUCACUCAGAAAUACAGUCACCACUGUCACAAAGCUGCCUAUUGCUGAUGCUAUCGAUUCCCUUCUUUUUCUACAGAAACAUCUUGGAGCUUGUCAAGCUUUACUGGAGGUGAUUUGCAGUUAAUUAAUUCAACAGACACUUUAAUCUUGCAAAUUCUUGACUUGUAAUAUUGUAACCAAGCUCCUGCAAGGGAACAUUAAUCAGUUAGUGAAAAAGGAGCACUUCCGUUCAGCCGUAGUACCAUGACGUGCACAGGCCUGAAGAGAAAUACCUCUGUGAAGUGGAGCGCUAGUGAAUUCCUGCUACCUGCUUCUUAUGGCUCACGCUAUGAAUAUUCACCUGCUUCAUUUGUUUUUUCCAGUAAACGCUGUUUUGAAAAAAAAGAAAAAUAUUCCCGGGGGCUUGCAUAGCUCAGAGAACGGAGUACUGGGUCGUGGAGACUUGCUUUAAAUGGAUUCAAAUCCACAUGUUUGGAAAUGAAAAUAAUGCACUGUCAUCUGUUGAAUAAUUGAUCUGUCUGAGUACAGUUGCUGCUUUUAUUUCAUUUCUUGAGACUACCAUUGUCAGCAUUGUAAUAACCAAUUUAUAAAAAUUGAGUUUUUAUUCAGUUUCAGAGGUAAAAUCUGCAUGGGUGCAGCUACUGAAUAAUUUGAUUCCUGCCUUCUUAGGUGGUGACAUUAGCAGUUCCAAACCGAGAUCCAUUUCUAUGUGGAAUUGGCUAUCCUGUUGCUUCUCAGGCCCUGCAAAACCUUGGUUACGAGCUCAAAGAUCACGAAUCUGAUAUUCUUUUUUUUUUUUUUUUUUUUUUUUUUUUGAGACAGAGUCUCGCUCUGUCGCAGGGGCUGGAGUGCAGUGGCACAAUCUCGGCUCACUGCAAGCUCUGCCUCCCAGGUUCACACCAUCCUUCUGCCUCAGCCUUCUGAGUAGGUGGGACUACAGGCGCCUGUCACCACGCCCGGCUAAUUUUUUUGUAUUUUUUAGUAGAGAUGGGGUUUCACCGUGUUAGCCAGAAUGGUCUCGAUCUCCUGACCUCGUGAUCUGCCCUCCUUGGCCUCCCAAAGUGCUGGGAUUACAGGCGUGAGCCACCACACCCGGCCCCGAUAUUCUUAAUGACUAAAUUUUCACAUAGAGGUAAACAGAUCAUCUCUUAAUUUAAUACAUGGUUCUUUCUCCCUUGCUUCUGGGUUUUGUUUUUUUUUUUUCAAAGAAAGAUUUGAGCUACGAGAUAAGAAUGAAGUUACCAGAAGUUAUCAGGUCAUAGUUUCAGAGUAUGCAAGAGAGUCGGGCCUUCAUAUGUUCUUGUAAAGUUUUCUGUCUAAUCUUUUGGUAUAACAAUUUUAGGAGUUCACCCUAGAUGAAAGAGUGGAAGUCAUCAGAUUUGUCAAUAAGCAGUCUAGAGGAAAAAUGAGAAGAGGAAGAAGCAGGGAUUCUUUUUCUUGUGUUUUGAAGAUGUUUCUCCUCCCAAAGCUAUCACCUUGGUAGUUAUCACCAAGAUGUAUAAUAGCAAGCACUACUGAAUGAUCUUCCCAGUUAUCAGCACUAGCAUCACGGCGAGUCAGUUUUCAGAACUAGCUCUUGGCGCAAGCCCUGAAAUAAAAUGGGGACAAAAAGUGGUCUACCACCAUGUGACUUAUUUUCUUUUUUUUUUUAAUUUUAUUAUUAUUAUACUUUAAGUUUUAGGGUACAUGUGCACAACGUGCAGGUUUGUUACAUAUGUAUACAUGUGCCAUGUUGGUGUGCUGUACCUAUUAACUCGUCAUUUAGCAUCAGGUAUAUCUCCUAAUGCUAUCCCUCCCCCCUCCCCCCACCCCACAACACUCCCCGGUGUGUGAUGUUCCCCUUCCUGUGCACGUGACUUAUUUUCAAUUGCCCAGCAAUGAAAACUAACAAGUUAAAGAAAAUGUUCAUUUUCUGAACCCCAGAGCCCACAUAGGUACAAAGAUACUCUGUAAUGUACAAUGAGGUGGCCAAUCGUGGGAAUAUAGGAGCAAUAAAUAGUCCUCUUAAGCAAGGUUCAUGGGUAAGAGUUACUCUAGCAGGAUUGGGUGUUGGGUCAGAGGGUAUCUAUUAAUGUAGAGGCCCAAGUAUGGUGAUGAAGAGAAAACCUGUCAGUGGCUCAUCCAUAGUAUUUGCCUUUUCACAGAGCAGAGAAGUUCAAAAUAGUCACAGCCAGUCCAUAACUAUAACAACAGACAUGUCCACUUUGGAAAGGCUAGGGCCUGACGAAAGUGGGAAAACAGAGAUGUCAGUGGUGUCAUGUCUAAGAGUGACUCUGUCAUUAGGGGAACCCACCCCCUGUGAUAGUUCUCCUUGACCACUGGUCCCUAUGGGCUCUGCAGGAGAGCUUCUCGUGGGUUCUAAGAUAAGGUAUUCCAAGGUAUUGUAAGUUACCCUUGUUUGUAGAACAUGAACCACUUAACCAUCCCUCCUUUUAACAGCAAUGAGAUUCAGGGUUACCAUGGCCUUACUCAUCUUCCCAUUGUAAAUAUAUCACAAUGUCACAAGAGCCUCUGUGUCCAAACACACUAAACUGGGUUUACAAGCAUUAGAAUCUUUCACUCAUAUUGUGAAUCUCAAUUCUGCCAGUCACCUAGUCUGUGUAUCUGUUCCCAAACUGGAAAAAAUAAUUCUUGAGAGAAUAAUUUUCAGAAUAAUGGAGGUGGAAAGAAAUGAACAGUUAAGCAAUUUUUCAACAUAGACAAAACCACUGGACCAUUGAUAGCCCUCAAGCUCUGAUUCUUCCUCCUGACUAAGUUUCUUUUCUUUGGGGGGCUUUCAACAUCUGAAUUUUCCAGAUGAUUGCGGAACCAUCGUCACUAAACCAAAGUAGACAAGGAGUUAUUAAAAAAUAAAGACUGUCCACAUGACUGCAAAUAUCCUGAUGAAAAGUGGCCAAGUAGAUCACUCAAGUGGUAAAUUUGGUCUUCAUGAUAUCAAACAUACGGAUAUUUGGAAAAGUCGAGAUGUUUGAAUCAUACAGUUUUCCGUCUGGGUGUCUGGUGUUUCUGGAUAGACAGACUGCUCCGGUGUUGUAAGUAAUGGAAUUGAACUUUCUUGCGCCGUAAGCAAUUGCUGGUCAUAUUCUGCUGCUAAAAGUCUCUUUGUUGUGCCAAGAGAAAUAAUGCAGAACAAAUGUUAUUUAAUUUUUAUUUACUUUCAGCAAACACAUGAAUGAAAGAGGUCAGGUAGGCUGUCCUGGGCAUUCUGGGCCUGGCUGCGGCACACCCUCCUUCACUUGGCCCCUGCCAGGCAAGAAACUUUCUAUUCAGUCUUUGCUAUCUUUCAUAAAUUGUAUCAUUGCUCUUCUGCUGUUCAUAUCAUCUUAGUUAUUCACAAAGUCUACUUGAUAAAAUGGCUCAAGGGAAAUACAAGUUUCUUAAGUUUUUAUUCUUCAAAUAGAAGUUUUAAUUUUAAGCAUUCCUUAUGAUAUUUUUUAAGCCUAAAAACCAUUCAAAUUGCUUGACAAAAUUAUUUCAUGGUGAAUUUUAUAAGGUUGAUAGAAGUAAAAGCUAUUUUUCCCAAAACAAACAAAAUACCAUACAUAGUUUUUUGGGUUUGGUUUGUUGAUGUCAUGCCAAUUUCCAAGCACCAACUGGUUACCACAAACAUGGGAAUAUUUAGUGAUAUCUUUGUAGUCAUCGUUAAAAUUCCUGGGAAAAAAAGAAAAAGUUUACGUCAAAGGAAAAUUCACCUCCCACAAGGAAAGUCUGAGAUGUUCAUCCUGACAUUUGCGUUCCUGAUUAUUUGUGGACAUUUCUUCAUUGUGACUGUAGGAAGCUGAGCUUGUUUCUCCUAAUUUGACACUGGGUUGGUGAGCAUUGUCUCAAAUUUUGUGCUUGCCUCAUUUAUGGUCCUGAAGCUUAGCAGAAAAACAGACAAGCUAUUCAGACCAGUUUUCUUUAAGAGCACUUAUGUUGCAGAACAUGAUACAAAUGAUUCACCGUGAGCAGGCACACAGAGUACGGAAAGGUAUUCAACUAUGCAAAGAUAUUGAGGGGAUUUCCAGAGAAAACUUAAAUGUUUUGAAGAUUUGUAGGUAGGGUUUUGAUUGUGUCACAUUCUACACUCAGUGCCAAGUUAGAAUGUCUUUAUGGGGAAGGCAAUAAAGUUACUUGUUGGGUCCUUCCUUCCCUUACAAACAGAAUGUUUUUAUGAAAUCAAAUGGAUCCUCCACUUUGUGUAGUAAGGACCCCCCAGGCCCCACAACAUCAUCACUGUGAGUCCUAUCGCAGAUGUGUGUACCAGCCCAAUUCAGUUUUGCUUUUCUUUUUCCCUAAGAUUUUUACUUCACCAAAUCCCAUUUCAAAUCUUUUUACCUUCAUGUUACCAACAGGAUGUUUAGUUGAAUCAGCAACAAAGACGUGACAACCUAUUGUCCUCCACAAAAGCAUGAGUCAUUUUAUUCAGUGAUCUUUGGUAGUACGAUAAUCAAUGGAAUUUAUGGUGUCGUAGAAAACCAAAAAUCCAUGUUGAAUAUAGUGACUGUCUUAAAUAUACUUAAAUAUGUUAUUCUACAAAACAAUAUCCUUUUACACUAUGGGAUGGAUUCCUUUCUGGAUGCAGGGAUGGGAGGGUCUAUGGGUCAGUGACUGGGACAAAGGAACUGGGAAUCUCUGCACAACUGAGCCCUAAUCCCUGGUCCAUCUCUCCAGCCUCAGAAACUCACCCUCAGCCUCAUUUUCCCCAUAUGCAAAAGAGAGAUAUUUAUUUACCUACCUCAUAGGGGUGUUGUGGAGAUUAGCUAGAUUUGCUAAAGUGCUUGUAGGUUAGAAAGUGCUGUCAUUCCUGAGAACUGGCAUUAACAGAAGAGAGCUGUGUGCAGCACGGAGGAAGUGGAGUCUGAGGAAUACAACAGCAACAACUCACCAAGCAGAGAAUACAAUGGUUCUUCAUCACUAUAUAAAACUAACACUUUUCCUUCAAAGGUCUAUGUAUAAUUUUCUUCAAUGAUUAGCUUUUUAAUGAGACAACUCCUUUCAUCCAGACAUUCAGAUGCUUUAUAUAAGUUGGCAAUUUUCCUGUUAACCAAACUGAAUUUUAUUAAAUGUUUAUUAAAAUGCACCCAGAAAACUUGUCUCCUCCUGAUGCCUGAGGGGUUUGCAUGCCUGAUCCCAAGCUGCAUUUUUUCAGAAUGCGUGCAUGAUGCCCCAGUUCUGUACUCAUGAUCACCAGGUGGCGUUCUGAAAUCCACUACUGGGGAAAGAUUUUUAACAGAUAUUAGUGAGAUUAGAGUUGGUGUCAUUUCCAUUGAGUAUCCUCUUCACCCCUAAGAUGACACAUCUUUACAACACAAUAAAAGAACGUAAAGCCUUAUUUCCACCUGUAACUCCUGAAUUGAUUCAUUUUCACGUUAUAACUACAUUUCAAAUAUUUCGGAGAAGUUUUUACACAGGGCUUCAGCUAUAUACUGAUAUACAUAUGCUUACAUGUGCUUAGGUGGGAAUUCUACUAAAGGAUAAAGGACACAGUGUGAAAACAACAUCAGAGAAUAUCCUGUACAACUUCCCCAAAAGUGACAAGUUUUCUUGUACUUAAAAAUUUAAUCCUGAUAAGAACUAAUGUGAAAUAACAUCAUUUUGGUUUAUAAAUAUUUGUAAUUUUUGAGACAUAGAGGCAAUAUCAUGAUAUAGGAAUACAUUCAUAAAACUAGACUAGCAAAGCAGAUAAUGUUUUCAUGAUAUGGCUUCAUGAGGCAAAGUUGUUGUACAUCAAUAUUAUCAUUGUGCCCUUAUUUAAGGAUUAUAUUCCAUUGUGAAAAAAAUGUGCACACUCUUAAAAACACAAAAUGGGUUUCAGAAAGUUUACCUUGAGAAGUGGGUUUGAAAUCAUCUUGUGCUUGGAGCUGACAUAAGAUACGCACUCAAUAUAAUCUCUUCUGGAUUCUAAAAUCUAAUUGGCAGUGAUAUUUCAAAGCCUUAACAUUUCAAGGUGGUUAAUUAAUAUCUAAUGCAUGGUAUUAAACUUUCUGAAGCAUGAAUUUAACCUAGGCAAUUAUCUGAUUCAUUUUUUUUAAAGUUUGUGCUGCCAAACCAGACUGAAGUAUUGUUUUUCUGGACUAAUACUAUGAGAAUAGUAAGUGAGUCAAAAAAUAAUUGGGACUGUCCUUUUUCCCCUGCCCACUUCCUAGUAUCAAUACUCCCCCAACCAGAAAUGCAGCAGAAUAUCCUUUUUGCUAUAAAGGAAAAUACUGUGUUUUUAUUUGUUUUUGCAGAAGAAAACUGGUGUUGCCUAUUUGGACUAGAUGUAGGGGCCUGGAAGAAGGAAGUGGCAGAUUCACAGGUGGGGUGACCAGGAUGGGAGGAAAAUAGUGGGGCGAGUAUGUCAUGGGGAGAUUUUGCCACAAAGAUACAAAACAGAAUUGAAGUGUGUUAGAGCUGGACAACCCUUUGAAAUGACAGAGUCUAGAUUCUUCACCAAACAGAUGAAAAGACAAGUAGAGACAACAUGUACUUGAGAUAUAAGCUAUACAUCUCAUCACUGGAAGAAAGGAGACUUCAGCCUCUUUUCAAGGCUUUCCAGACCACAUGGAACUCUCCAGAGCCCUCCUUGAAAGUUUUUAGAAAAACUACCAUUUUCAGCAAAGAUUCAUGUGAUUAUGCUGCUGAGGACCAGUCAUUCUGUAAACAUCACAUAUGUGAUGCUUUGUAAAUGUAUUAAUUGUGGUCAAUUUUCAUGGAUAUUUCCCAUUAACAUUGUAUUCCAUGAACAAGUGAUAGAAAACAUAUGGAAAUUCUCUUUUGAUCAAAAGGAGUGUCUCCCAAUUAGUUUACGUGUGUUAGUAUUGCUGACAUAUUAUUAUCAUCACAAAAUUCCUUUUAUAUCUAGAUGGUAUCAAAUAAGAAAAAAAUGCAUCAUUUGGUCAAUUGCUUAUUGAAGAUCCCAGCUGAAGCCUUUCUUUGGUAAAGAGCGCAGAAAGAGACCAUAGCUAUUCUUGGAUGAGAACCUUGCCUCUACUAAAUAGUUUCUGCUUUUCCUCUCUGUAGCCAGACAGCUCAAUAGCCUAGGGAGAGUCGAUGAAGGAUAUGCAAAUUACAUUUUUCCCAUUCUCAGAACAAAGACAGCAACCAAUGAGCCAGAGGUUUCUUCUCUCUUUGAAACCAAAUAGCACGCUGAAUUUAGGGCUAUGACAAAAAUGUUGUUAAAGCAAGAGCAAAAUCAUCCUUCCUAUGGAUUCUUUUCUCAGUGUUUACUUAAUUCUUUUUGCAGUUUGGAUUGGAGUUUCUAGUAAUGAUAAUUAAUGCCAUUUUACAUGAUAGCUUCAAUGCAGAAAUGGUGUGAGCCUGAGUUACAAAUGACAUGACUAGGGAUACAAACUUCGUCUGUACUAACAUCCUACCAAGCAGAUUGGAAACAAAUACUACUACCACUAAUAUUCUGAUGUAAUUAAUAACAUCUAAUAGAAAAAUAGAAACAUCGUGCUUAGCAUGAAACCAUUGCACAAUAUAAACCUGCUCCCAAAUGGCAAGGAUUUUUGCUACCAAUAUUUGUUCUUAAUUCUCCAGUUAUUUUAAGUAAAUAAGUUUCACAUCUAACUACCUCAGCUACUGUUGUUUUAUUUAGAAACAUGAAACCAUGCACUUUGUAAUCAAUAAGUCUUUUGUUUAACAUUUCAAAAGGAUAUUUGGUGCAAAGCAAUUUUCAAAAAUUUGUACAUGAUAUACACCACCCAACCUCAGGAGGUUGUACUUAAUUUUGUUUGUUUGUUUCUAAGGUUGGUUUUGGGUAAAAUCCUCAUUUCCACUCAACAUCAAGAUAAGCUGCUCUAUAUUUGCUUAAUUUGCCUUAAACAUUUUGUGCUCCUUUCCCUGUUCAAUUUUUUUGUUUUGUUUUAAAUCUAUCUCUGAAAAAAAAAUGGAACAGGUGGCAGGUGAACAGCAAAUGGAAGAGAAUGGACCAGUAAUUUCUCAGUCCCCUGUUGUCAACUAUCUGCAUGACAUUCUGAUUGUGCAAAAAUGCCAUUCCUGUGCUUCCCCCUCCAUUACAGAAUAAGGUCCGAGAGACCCCACGAGUGUGCGUAGGGAACGGUGUAGACAUUUCCCCCAGUAUGAGCACAGUGCCUGGACCUGAAUGAUCAUCUUGGCAGUUCUUGUGCUUUUACUUUGUAAACAUUGUACAAAUGUAUUUGGAAUUUUAUUUGAAAUGGAGACUUAAACUAGUUAUUAAAUUUGUUUCCUUCCUGUAAAUAUAUAUAUUCAAAUUCCAUGUAUCCAAACAUCCCUUUAGCGUUCAGAUUGUAAGUGUGUCUUUAUUCGCGGGAGGCCACUGUCAGCAGGCAGUGACCCCCAGUGCCCUAGUUUGAAGCACAGUGUGUGGAGUAUUUGAUGUACUACAGUACCAUAGUUAUUUUGGUCUGUUAAGUAAGUUGCAAUUUGUGAUGAAAUGAAGUGGAAAGUAGUACUUCAUAAUGAACAAAUUUCCUUGGUUACAUGGUUUUUCUUGUAAAACUUAAAGAAAAAAAAAGAAAACUUGAAAUUUUA